GCCUAGGGCAGUGCUGGGAGAGAAGUACCCCCACCAGCAGAUUAUAUUUCCCAGCCUGUCUGUCUCAGAGAUUCCAGUCUAUGUUUCCCAUCCAUUGAGGGCUCAGUUACCCUCGGGCUGUUUCCCACCAGUUUCCACUCUUCCUUAGAUAUCCCAUGCAGAAACUCCUGGCAGCUCACAGAUUCCCCAUUGAGCCCAACCCCUUCAUGUAGGAAAAGGGGGAAAAAUGAAGAAAACUGGUCUUGAAAGCCCGCAGACUUUCAUACCACAAGGAAUGUGUUGACCACAUGCAUCUUAAACCAGACGAGCGACGUUUGUCCAGUCCUUCAACUUACUGAUAUUCAGCCAUAUCUGUUUCAUGCUGUAAAUUAAAACCUCAGAACCAGGAGGUUUUUCCCAAUCCUUCUCACAAACAGGGAUUAAGUUGUAAAUACACAGUUGCUUACAUAUUAAAUUGUAUUUUGUUUAUGGCAUAAUUUAUCUGCAGGAGACAUUGAUUUUCACAGCAAAUUCCUUUAUCUUUAAAAUUUUCAGCCUAUAUAUGGGUAUGCAGCCACUGAAAUAUUAUUAUAGGUGAGGCUACCUCUGAAUUGCUAAGGUCACAAAACAAAAUCUCCCAUCUUUUUGUUUUAAUUUCCCAUAAAAUAAAAGAUAUUUUACAUUUAUAUCCCCUAUUACUGGAACACCUACAGAUUAUCCAGAUGUUUGUAUUAUUAUAUGUCCUCCAUACCUGAUGGCAGGCAUAGUUAUCUUUUAAACCUGAAUGCAGGGGUAAUUAACAACACUCUCAAAACUUUUUCUGUAGAUAGCUUGCAUUGAGAAGACGGAUUCCUUGUGGGCUUAAAUCCUACUGUCUGCAGUUGACCGAAUAUAAGAGAACAACAUCUGGCCUAAUUUAUCUUUAGGCAAAAUUUAAUAAUGCUGAAUGGCAACCUCUGGGAAAAAUCUAAGUAAGACUUGUUGUGAGUCCUAAUUUAGGGUUGGCUAAAGGUAACUCUUACUUUGUAUUUCUUUUUUCAAAGGGAUGGGUAUUUUGAUCACAUGAAAGUUAAUAAUUUUUCUUCGUUCUGUCAUCAAAAUGUGAUAUUACAGUAUAAUGAGCUCCCAACCUGGUUGUAAGCAGAACUCAGCUUGUAAAAUCAGGACUAAGGAAGGCUAGGAAGCAACAGGGACUAUCUGAUUUCAUGCAGAAUCUUUUGUUGGCAAAGGCAAGUUUUAAUAUUCCAUUGACUUCUCAAAGAGAUCCAACCCCUAUUUCAUAGCAACAAACAUUGGCUGAUUGAAACCAGUCCUGCUUGCUUAUAAAUAUACCUUAAUUCCUCUAGCACAUAGUUUAAGAAACAAGACCAGAAAUGAGGAGUAAACUGGGGAGGGUUGGAAAACUGGGGUAAUAUUAAGGUAGGUAGUACAUCAAGAAGCAUGUAGAAAUAUUUGCCCUGAAUUCGUUUAGCAUAAAUCUUAAUUUAUAUAUAUAUAAAUGGGGUCUCACUAUGUUGACCAGGCUGGUCUCUCAUACUCCUGACCUCAAGUGAUCCUCCCAUCUUGGCCUCCCAAAGUGCUGGGAUUACAGGCAUGAACCACCAUGCCUGGCCUAUUUAGCACAAAUCUUGAUGCAGAUAUUUUAAUUACAUCAUAAUUGAGUAUAGUAAAUCAGGCUGGGAGUUCUUUGAGUUGGUUUGUAGUAUAAACCAUUAUGGUAAAUAUUUAUGCAUGACUCAAAUUGGAAACAGGAACACACAUUUUGCUUAAGUCUACUGGUCUGUAGAAAGCCUGUGGUCUAAACUCUAAACUCUUAGGAUACCUGCUUCAUAUUUUUAAAAUGUUAGUCCUAUUUUUGAAGCCUUGGAAUCAGGAAUUUCUUCACCUAUUACUCAUCAAAGUUCUAGGUAAAUAACUUUUACCGCUAGAAUUAUUUAUAACUUUGCCCGUGGACUCCCAUUGUUGUAAAAUGUUUAUUUUUUUAGAUAUUACUUCUGGAUGGGUCAAGUGCAUAUUUAACAAAGAAAUACACCCUGCUUCUCAGAAUUUUUGUUUAUUAAGAGUUUGCAUUGCCAGUGAUGAGGUUUUAGAAAUUGCUAUCUUUCUGUUAAUCUAAAGGAAGGAGAUAAGUUAGCAUCUGACUUAAAAGCAUUUAUUAUAUAUCCUGUAUCUUUUUAAAAUAUCCUAUGAAAGGAAUCAACUAUAGGCUCAAUAAUUAGUAUAAUGAACACAUUGGUCAUGAAACUUUGGUCAUCUAACCAAUUUAAUGAAAAGGAGAGUUUAUUGGAAGACUCAUAAGUUAGAAGCCAUUGCAGCAAAAUGGGAGGUUCUAGGUAAUACUUGGAAAGUAAGAAUGAAAGUAACUAGGACUCUCCCAUCCUCUCUCUGCAGAGUAUGCUUAUUUUCUGAGCCUGGCUCACAUGCCUACGAACAUAGCUUCCAGCAAAUCUCAGGCUCUCCUCACAUAGUAUCAUUACCAGAAAGUAAUCAAGAUGUGUUUUCUUGAGUUUUAGGGUUGUACAUCCUGGAGAAGAUUAAUGAUUGGCUCUCCCUGUGUCCCCAACUCCAGCCAUCCCUCCUUCCCAUCCUUAAUAGGAAGCUCUUCAGGAGUUGUUUCUUCCUGAAGGAAUAUGACAGGGAUAUGUCAGCUUCAGGAAUGUAACAGCUUCCAUUCAAAUCAAAAUGAGAAAGGGCAUUCUUUGGAAGAAGGAAGUAGGGAAUAAUAAACUGAGUACAUCAAUUCUUUCUUGUCAAUUCAUUGUCUUCUUUUUUUUUUCAUUAGGCAAGUAUUACACACCUACAUGUGCUAGUUACUGGAAAUAUAGCAGCAAACACAUAUCAAGAUAACAAUUCCAUAGAAUCUGAAUUAUAAAACCACCACUAGAAACAGGGUAGGCAGCGGUCAUUUCUAUGUAGAGUAGAUUAGCAUUUUGAAUGAAUAUGAAAGAAGACAUAUAGCUUAGUUCCUUCCUUUCAUUUUAAAUCUAUUUCUAAGUAAAUUAAAUGCUUGCCACCCUCCCUUCCCCCACUGUAGUAAGCCAGAGAGUAAAUGUCUCCAGCAAUGGUAAUGGCAAAUUUUAUUGUAUUUCAUUUUAGUGUAUGUGUGUGCUUGGUAAAUAUUUGUUAACUGAAUGGAUUAUUGAGGUGGUGGUGGUGGUGUCCAUCUAUAGUCAGGAGAAAAGAAUUACUAUUAACUGUGACAAAAUAAACAUCAUUGUUAUUCAACAUUUAAGUAGGCAGAAUCAAAUAAUUUCAUAUAACAAAGUCAUUUUAUACGAUUAUCUAAAGAUAUAUUUUACAACUAAUUUCUUCUGGCAGAUACAUCUGGAUGCUGUGUCAUUUCAGACUAGUUUGUGGGAAUAACAUUGAAUAAUUUUUCUGACUCAGAUUGAAUGAUGAGUAAUGUUUGCUUUGGAAAAAUUUCAGUCUUCCUGUAUUUUAUUUUCUUCACUAUGAUUACAGUAUAAGGCAUGUAACUGUUUCUGUUAUUGGUUGAGUAUUCAUAUUUGUUUUGUUUUUGAGCUGACCUUCUUUCUCUCUCUGUUUCAUUCAUUCAUUCAUUUACUCAUUUUGAGACAGGGUCUGGCUCUGUUACCCAGGCUGGAGUGCAGUGGCAUGAUCUUGGCUCACUGCAAUCUCCACCUCUCAGACUCAAAAGAUCCUUCCACCUUAGCCUCCUAAGUAGCUAGGACUAGCACGUGCCACCACGCUUGGCUAAUUUUUUUAUCUUUUUGUAGAGACCAGGGUUUCACCAUGUUGACCAGGCUGAUCUCGAACUCCUGAGCUCGAGCGAUCUGCCCGCCUUGGCCUCCCAGUGUGCUAGGAUUACAGACGUGACCCACUGCGCCUAGCCUUGAGCUGACUUUUAAAUCAGCUGUUAACAACUAUAUAACUUAUAUAAUACAUGCAUAAGUCAUAUAAAUUACAUAAUAUGUAGAGUCUCCAGGAUUACAAUUAUUAACGCUAAUAUUUUUAUAUGGCGGGGAUGUGGGUGGGACUUUGUGGUGUACAUGUAUAUGUACACCACAGACACUGGAAUAUAUGCGUCCUCUCUAUGUAUUGUUCUUCAACAUGUUUAUUUUUACUUACCACUUUCUCAUGGACAUCCUCCCAUGUCAGUACAUAUUUUCUUAUUUCUUACCUUAUUAUUUCUAUUAUUUUAUGGUAUGUAUGUACCUUCAUUUAUUUAACCAUCUCCCUCUUAGACUACGUCUCAUUAUUUUGGAGUCAUAAUCUCAUAUAAUGCUUCAUUGUACAUGCAGGAUAGGCUGUGAAUUUUUGUAAGAAAAAUACCUAAAGGUAGAUGAAGUUCAGUAAGUGAGACUGCCUACCUUUUACAUUGUAAUAGUACUGUUAAAUUAUCCUCCAAGUGAGAUUUUACCAUUUGAUACAAGGCAGUAUAUUGUGAUGGUGAAACACUUGGACAAGGAGGCAUGGAUUUGAAUCCCAGUUCUGCUUCUUACCUGGGAAUAACCUGGUAUAAGUGAAUUAAAAGUGAAUUAAUGUAUUGGUGUCUCAGUUCUCUCAUCUACAAAAAAAAAAAAACAAAAAAAACAAAAAACAAACAAAACAAAUCUACCUGAGUGAUUGUGAAAUUAAAUGUCUUAACAUAAGUCAAGUUCUUAGAAAAAUGCCUAGCCUAUUUUGAUUACGAAAUGCUUUCUAGCAUUAUGUAUUAGCUGCUCUUAUUAACACUAGCAUCUUAUAUGGAUUCCCAAGAUUUAAAACUUUAGGGUCUUGACUGAUUGCUGCUCUUCACGUUAUCCUGCAGGGAAUGCUGGGUAUCCCUGUUGUCUGUUUCCAUAAGGACAGGUGUUUAGUAUUCAUAUGUAGGCAAAAAUAUACACUAAGCACCUUAAUUUUCAUAAUAUUGUAUUAAUCCUACAUCUGCAAAUAUUGUUUUCAGAGUUGUUAUAUAUCUAUCUAUACUAGUAGUAGUAAAAUAUAAACCCCAAAUUGUUAGAGUAUCUAAUCUUGAUUUAAUCAUAUUAGAUCUUGGGAAGAUUGUCUACUUUAAUUAUUUCAUCUAAUAUUCUCAUUUAUAUUUUUGUGUUAUGUUUAGAUUUUUAUGGGAGGUUCUAUAACAAAACUUAUUAUAUGUCCCAUGUUUGCUUUUACUUAGCCCUCCUUGUAAAUAUUGUCCAUUGCCCCCCAGUGCCUCUGUAUAAAAAUGUCUAUGUGAGACACUUCUCUUAGUUUAGAAAUAAGAAAGCGUUUAUCUGCUCUGACAAACUCAUGUUUCUUUCAUUCAGCUAAUGAGAGUUAACUAAUGUCUGCCUCUACAUUUUAACUGCCAUAAAAUUGGGACAAUGUUCAAGAUCAAAGUCACAGCAACUUUAUCAUCGGGCAUGAUUUCUCAUUUUUGAAGCAUUUCACUGGAUUAGUCUCUUUUAAACUAGUGCAAGUUUCUUUCAAGGAGAUGUGAUAAGAAAAGUUACAUGAGAUAAGUUAUCUGGGAUAAGAAAUGAUGACAUAUGAACCUCGAUGACAAGACACUGUAAGAAUCUGCAGGCACUAGAAAAACACCCCAACUCACCAAUGACAGCAAAGCAGAUAUUGGAAGUCAUUCAGAAAGAAGGGUUAAAAGAAACAAGAAAUGGAACCUCUCCAUUAGCCUGUCUGAAUGCAAUGCUUCACACUAACACUCGAAUAGGGGAUGGAACAUUCUUCAAAAUCCCUGGAAAGUCAGGCCUCUAUGCUCUCAAAAAAGAGGAGUCGUCAUGCCCAGCAGAUGGCACGUUGGAUUUAGUCUGUGAAUCUGAAUUGGAUGGUACAGAUAUGGCCGAGGCAAAUGCCCAUGGAGAAGAAAAUGGAGUUUGUUCGAAGCAGGUAACUGAUGAAGCAUCUUCCACUCGAGAUUCAAGCCUUACUAACACAGCAGUGCAAAGCAAGUUAGUGUCUUCCUUCCAGCAGCACACCAAAAAGGCUCUUAAACAGGCUUUGAGGCAGCAGCAGAAAAGAAGAAAUGGAGUCUCAAUGAUGGUAAACAAGACUGUUCCUCGUGUUGUUUUGACACCAUUAAAGGUGUCUGAUGAGCAGUCGGAUUCGCCUUCAGGAUCUGAAUCUAAAAAUGGUGAAGCAGACAGUUCAGAUAAAGAAAUGAAACAUGGGCAAAAAUCUCCCACUGGAAAACAAACAAGUCAGCACUUAAAACGAUUAAAAAAGUCUGGUUUAGGGCACUUGAAAUGGACCAAAGCUGAGGACAUUGACAUAGAAACCCCAGGAUCUAUUCUUGUCAACACUAACUUGAGGGCAUUAAUAAAUAAACAUACGUUUGCUUCCUUACCUCAGCAUUUUCAACAAUACCUCCUGCUUUUGCUCCCAGAAGUGGAUAGGCAGAUGGGAAGUGAUGGAAUUUUACGCCUCAGUACUUCAGCUCUAAAUAAUGAAUUCUUUGCAUAUGCAGCACAAGGGUGGAAACAGCGACUGGCAGAAGGAGAGUUUACCCCAGAAAUGCAGUUGCGGAUAAGGCAAGAAAUUGAGAAGGAAAAGAAAACAGAACCUUGGAAAGAAAAAUUCUUUGAGAGGUUUUAUGGAGAAAAGCUGGGCAUGUCAAGAGAGGAAUCUGUGAAGCUCACUACUGGACCAAACAACGCUGGAGCUCAAAGUAGUUCUUCAUGUGGGACUUCUGGCCUUCCAGUUUCUGCACAGACAGCCUUGGCAGAACAACAGCCAAAAAGCAUGAAAAGCCCAGCUUCUCCAGAGCCUGGUUUCUGUGCUACUCUUUGCCCUAUGGUAGAAAUUCCACCUAAAGAUAUAAUGGCAGAAUUGGAGUCAGAGGAUAUCUUGAUCCCUGAAGAAUCUGUAAUUCAGGAGGAAAUUGCAGAAGAGGUAGAGACUAGUAUCUGUGAAUGCCAGGAUGAAAAUCAUAAGACAAUACCUGAAUUUUCUGAGGAGGCUGAAAGUCUAACCAAUUCUCAUGAAGAACCCCAAAUAGCACCUCCUGAAGAUAACUUGGAAUCCUGUGUUAUGAUGAAUGAUGUUUUAGAAACUUUGCCUCAUAUUGAAGUUAAGAUAGAAGGGAAGUCAGAAUCACCCCAGGAAGAAAUGACAGUUGUUAUCGAUCAGUUAGAAGUCUGUGACUCUCUUAUUCCUUCCACUUCAUCUAUGACUCAUGUCAGUGACACAGAACAUAAGGAGUCAGAAACUGCAGUAGAGACCAGUACCCCCAAAAUAAAAACAGGGUCAUCUUCUCUAGAAGGCCAGUUUCCAAAUGAAGGAAUUGCUAUAGAUAUGGAGCUACAGAGUGACCCUGAAGAACAGCUUUCAGAAAAUGCCUGCAUCUCUGAAACGUCCUUUUCUUCUGAGAGCCCAGAGGGAGCCUGUACCAGCCUGCCUUCUCCAGGAGGGGAAACACAGUCCACAUCAGAAGAAUCAUGUACUCCAGCCUCCCUUGAGACAACAUUUUGUUCUGAGGUAUCUAGCACUGAAAAUACAGACAAAUACAACCAGAGAAAUUCCACUGAUGAAAACUUUCAUGCAUCUUUGAUGUCAGAAAUAUCUCCAAUAUCCACUUCACCUGAAAUAUCAGAAGCAUCUCUUAUGUCCAACUUACCAUUAACAUCUGAAGCAUCACCAGUAUCCAACUUACCUUUAACAUCAGAAACCUCACCGAUGUCUGACUUACCUUUAACAUCAGAAACUUCUUCAGUGUCUUCCAUGCUUCUCACCUCUGAGACCACUUUUGUAUCCAGUUUGCCACUUCCUUCAGAAACAUCUCCAAUUUCCAACUCUUCCAUAAAUGAGAGAAUGGCACAUCAGCAAAGAAAGUCACCUUCUGUAUCUGAAGAGCCACUCUCCCCGCAGAAAGAUGAGUCUUCCGCCACUGCCAAACCUCUGGGAGAGAACCUUACCUCCCAGCAGAAGAAUCUGUCUAAUACUCCCGAACCCAUCAUAAUGAGUUCUUCUUCCAUUGCUCCUGAAGCAUUUCCGUCUGAAGAUUUGCACAAUAAGACCCUGAGUCAGCAAACCUGUAAAUCACAUGUUGACACUGAGAAGCCCUACCCUGCUUCAAUUCCAGAACUUGCUUCUACUGAAAUGAUAAAAGUUAAAAAUCAUAGCGUCCUGCAAAGAACAGAAAAAAAAGUGUUACCUUCACCAUUGGAAUUAUCUGUCUUUUCUGAAGGGACAGAUAAUAAGGGAAAUGAGCUUCCAUCUGCUAAAUUACAGGACAAGCAAUAUAUCUCAUCAGUGGAUAAGGCUCCAUUUUCAGAAGGCUCUAGAAAUAAAACACAUAAGCAAGGGAGUACACAGAGUCGGUUAGAAACCUCACAUACUUCCAAGUCAUCAGAGCCCUCCAAGUCACCUGAUGGGAUAAGAAAUGAAAGUAGAGAUUCAGAGAUAUCAAAGAGAAAAACUGCAGAGCAACACAGCUUUGGAAUCUGUAAGGAAAAGAGAGCUAGGAUAGAAGAUGAUCAGUCAACCCGGAACAUAUCAUCUAGCAGCCCACCUGAGAAAGAACAGCCUCCCAGAGAGGAACCAAGGGUUCCCCCUCUCAAGAUUCAGCUUUCCAAAAUUGGGCCACCUUUUAUAAUCAAGAGCCAACCAGUCUCCAAACCUGAGUCUCGAGCAUCCACUAGCACAUCUGUCAGUGGCGGGAGGAACACAGGAGCCAGGACCCUCGCAGAUAUCAAGGCCCGGGCCCAACAAGCUCGGGCCCAGCGAGAGGCUGCUGCAGCUGCUGCUGUGGCUGCUGCAGCGAGCAUUGUCUCUGGAGCCAUGGGAAGUCCAGGAGAGGGUGGAAAGACGAGAACUCUGGCACACAUCAAAGAGCAGACAAAGGCUAAGCUCUUUGCAAAGCAUCAAGCUCGAGCCCAUCUCUUCCAGACCUCUAAAGAGACCCGGUUGCCUCCUCCGCUCAGCUCAAAGGAAGGGCCUCCAAACUUAGAAGUCUCUUCUACCCCUGAAACAAAAAUGGAAGGUUCGACUGGUGUCAUUAUUGUCAAUCCAAACUGUAGAUCUCCUAGCAACAAGUCUGCCCACCUCCGGGAGACCACCACUGUACUACAGCAGUCUCUUAACCCAAGUAAACUUCCAGAAACUGCCACUGACUUAUCUGUGCAUAGUUCUGAUGAAAACAUACCUGUGUCACAUUUAUCUGAGAAAAUUGUUUCAUCUACCUCUUCUGAAAAUAGCAGUGUGCCCAUGCUUUUUAAUAAAAAUUCUGUCCCUGUAUCUGUUUGCAGCACUGCUAUAUCGGGAGCAAUUAAAGAACAUCCCUUUGUGAGUUCUGUUGAUAAAUCCUCUGUCCUAAUGUCUGUUGACAGUGCAAACACUACAAUUUCUGCUUGUAAUAUAAGCAUGUUAAAAACCAUCCAGGGAACUGACACUCCAUGCAUAGCCAUUAUACCAAAAUGUAUUGAAAGCACUCCCAUUUCAGCCACUACAGAGGGCUCCAGCAUAUCAAGCUCCAUGGAUGAUAAGCAGUUACUAAUAUCAAGCAGCAGUGCUAGUAACUUAGUCUCCACUCAGUACACCUCUGUGCCAACUCCCUCCAUCGGAAACAAUUUGCCAAACCUCUCCACUAGCUCUGUCUUGAUUCCCCCAAUGGGAAUUAACAACAGAUUUCCUUCUGAGAAGAUAGCCAUACCUGGGAGUGAAGAACAGGCCACUGUAUCCAUGGGUACCACUGUGAGAGCAGCCCUCAGCUGCAGUGAUUCUGUAGCGGUCACAGACUCUCUGGUUGCACACCCGACCGUCGCAAUGUUUACUGGAAACAUGCUGACAAUAAACUCUUAUGAUAGUCCUCCCAAGUUAAGUGCUGAAAGCUUGGACAAAAAUUCAGGGCCUCGAAACAGGGCAGAUAAUUCUGGAAAACCUCAGCAACCACCAGGGGGCUUUGCACCAGCAGCCAUAAACCGAUCAAUUCCGUGUAAAGUCAUCGUUGACCACAGCACCACGCUGACCUCCAGUUUGUCUCUGACUGUCUCCGUUGAAAGCUCAGAAGCCAGCUUGGACCUGCAGGGCAGACCAGUGAGGACAGAGGCAUCCGUACAGCCCGUGGCGUGUCCUCAGGUGUCUGUGAUUAGCAGGCCUGAGCCAGUUGCCAACGAAGGUAUAGAUCACAGUUCCACUUUCAUUGCUGCUUCGGCAGCAAAACAAGACAGUAAAACAUUGCCGGCCACCUGCACAAGUCUCCGAGAAUUACCCCUUGUUCCAGAUAAAUUAAAUGAGCCGACUGCUCCCAGUCAUAACUUUGCUGAGCAGGCACGUGGCCCAGCUCCUUUCAAAAGUGAAGCAGACACAACCUGUAGCAAUCAGUAUAACCCAAGUAACCGGAUUUGCUGGAAUGAUGAUGGGAUGAGGAGCACAGGACAGCCUCUGGUUACUCACUCGGGUUCAAGUAAACAAAAAGAAUAUCUAGAGCAAAGCUGUCCAAAGGCUAUCAAAACUGAACAUGCCAACUACUUGAACGUGUCAGAACUUCAUCCCAGGAAUCUUGUAACAAAUGUUGCUCUUCCUGUGAAAUCUGAACUUCACGAAGCAGACAAGGGCUUUAGAAUGGACACUGAAGACUUCCCUGGCCCUGAGCUGCCUCCUCCGGCUGCAGAGGGAGCCUCUAGUGUACAACAAACACAGAACAUGAAAGCUUCCACCUCAAGUCCCAUGGAAGAGGCUAUUUCCUUGGCUACCGAUGCCCUGAAGAGAGUCCCUGGUGCAGGGAGCUCAGGCUGUCGUCUGUCCUCUGUGGAGGCUAACAAUCCGCUGGUGACGCAGUUACUACAGGGCAACCUGCCUUUGGAAAAAGUGUUGCCACAGCCCAGAUUGGGAGCCAAGCUUGAAAUCAACAGGCUUCCAUUGCCUCUUCAAACUACCUCAGUGGGUAAAACAGCACCAGAGAGAAACGUUGAAAUUCCGCCCAGCUCUCCAAAUCCAGAUGGUAAGGGCUACUUGGCAGGGACUCUGGCACCACUCCAAAUGAGAAAGCGAGAAAACCACCCCAAAAAGAGAGUAGCUAGGACUGUAGGAGAACACACUCAAGUUAAAUGUGAACCAGGAAAAUUGUUGGUGGAGCCAGAUGUUAAAGGGGUGCCUUGUGUCAUCAGUUCCGGCAUCAGUCAGCUAGGACACAGCCAGCCAUUUAAGCAAGAAUGGCUAAACAAGCACUCCAUGCAGAACAGAAUUGUUCACAGCCCUGAGGUCAAACAGCAAAAGCGGCUGCUCCCCUCGUGUAGCUUCCAGCAGAACCUAUUUCAUGUUGACAAGAAUGGCGGCUUCCACACUGACGCUGGUACCUCACACAGACAGCAGUUUUACCAAAUGCCUGUGGCUGCCAGGGGCCCCAUUCCUACUGCAGCUCUGUUACAGGCCUCUUCCAAGACCCCAGUGGGGUGUAAUGCAUUUGCCUUCAACAGGCAUCUUGAACAGAAGGGAUUGGGAGAGGUUAGUCUUUCCUCAGCACCUCACCAGCUAAGGUUAGCCAACAUGUUAUCCCCCAAUAUGCCCAUGAAAGAAGGUGAUGAGGUGGGAGGCACUGCACACACAAUGCCAAACAAAGCACUAGUACAUCCGCCGCCGCCACCGCCUCCCCCUCCCCCUCCACCCUUGGCUUUGCCCCCGCCUCCCCCCCCACCACCUCCGCUACCUCCACCUCUCCCUAAUGCAGAAGUCCCAUCUGAUCAAAAACAACCUCCAGUUACCAUGGAAACCACUAAGAGACUUAGUUGGCCACAGUCCACGGGCAUAUGUAGCAAUAUAAAAUCGGAACCUCUUUCUUUUGAGGAAGGUUUAAGCAGCAGCUGUGAACUGGGCAUGAAACAAGUUUCCUAUGACCAGAAUGAAAUGAAAGAACAGUUAAAAGCAUUCGCGCUAAAAAGUGCAGAUUUCUCUUCCUAUUUGCUUUCUGAGCCACAAAAGCCUUUUACCCAAUUAGCUGCUCAGAAAAUGCAGGUGCAGCAACAACAGCAGCUCUGUGGAAAUUAUCCAACAAUACACUUUGGUAGCACGAGUUUCAAAAGGGCAGCAUCUGCAAUUGAAAAGUCCAUUGGGAUUUUGGGAAGUGGCUCCAAUCCUGCCACAGGCUUGUCUGGUCAGAACGCUCAGAUGCCCGUUCAGAACUUUGCCGACAGCAGCAAUGCAGAUGAAUUGGAACUGAAAUGCUCUUGCCGGCUGAAAGCCAUGAUUGUGUGCAAAGGCUGUGGGGCCUUCUGCCAUGACGACUGCAUAGGUCCUUCAAAACUUUGUGUAGCAUGCCUGGUUGUACGAUAAGAGCUGAGUGAAAGAUGCAGUAUCCCUUUUCCACACGGAAAAGCCAAAUAGCAUCAGCAACAACAAAUAGAAUAAUGCAGUGGUUUCUAUCAUGCUAAUUUAUUUUGCUUUGGAGCAGGUACCUUUCCUCUAUGGCAUUAUUUUCUUGCAUUUCUCAUAAAGGGGAGGAUGCAUCCCAACUGAAUGGCUCACUGGCAUGUCUUUUAUGUGUUCAGUUGCCAUUCCUAGCUUUGGAAAGUUUCUAUCUGUCCAUGUGUAUACAAGUCAAUGCCCCAUUUUUGUUUUUCUUUUAACCGAGGUGUAGAUAGGAAAAGGACAUUUUUAAUUACUUAAUAACCGGAAAUGCAGAUGUGUAAGGAGAAUGAGAGGAAUGAGUUAAAGUGGUUAUGCAUUUUUCUAUAGAUGAGCCAUUACAGCAAGGAAUUUUACAGUUGACUUCUCUGAACCUAGCUUUACCACAGUGAUUAAAUCCUAUUUAGAAAGGGGAAUCUGAUUUAAAUGUGUGAUUCCUUGUAUUUGCUCCUAUCACAAAAGAUAUAUUAAAGGAGGUAUGCCAUUAAUGAAAUCCACUGUCCUGAGUAUUAUCUUUCCUCCUGUUGUACUUUCUCAGAGACUAUGGCAGAAUAUCUGGAUCUUCCUUGGAUUUUGUACACAUAUUGUAGUGAAAUGUGUCCUACAUCUGAAAUUGCAUGGGACUCAUGCCCAGCAAUCUGGUUCUAGGCCUUUGACACCUGAUAAUAUGAGAGCAAUUGGCCAGCCAAUAGCCAUAAGCCCAGAGGAUUUUAGAGCUUCAUGUGUGGCUUUUAAGAGCAGGUUUGAAAAAAAAAAAAAAAAGACCCUAAACUUCAAAGCAAGGAAAUAAGAUGCUGUAUAUGCACACAUAAAUGCAUUGAUAAUGUAAAUAUCCUAUUCACGCUAAUGAAUUACUAGAUAUUAAAAGUGGGGGGUGGAAAUCAUUGUAGCCCUUUAUUGAUGACACCCAUUCAUUCUGGCUUCAGACCUUGCAGAGGUUGGCCAUAUCUUUUUAAAAGUGUCAUUGAUGAUAAAAGGGACUACCCAAGGCUAAAGCGUCAACAUUUUUCAGAACAAUUGCUUUUCUCAUUAUUUACAACCUAUAUAAUUCAACUUUGAAAUAACCCUUAUUUUGAAAAAAACUGUUCUAGGUAUGGCAUGUUUUGUUUUUUCCCUCAGGUAUAUUCAAUACAUUCUUCAUAUUUGGGGGAACUGCUUUUGAAAAAGGGAUACUGCAUCUUAACAGUUAUCUUCAGUGUGCAUCCAGUAAAGUCUGCGUGUUGAGUAUUUGAGCUACAUUCCAUAUAUUUUGGCCACCCUCAUACCAGAGGACAGCCGUAGUUCAGGAGGCUCUGUUUUCAAAAGCAAGUUCAAAAGCACAUGCACAUUGAGGGAAGAUGAAAGAAAACAAAAACCAACCAUGCCCAUUUAACUUCAGAUUACAGAGCACAAAAUGUGGAGUGCCAUUAACCCAUUGAUUGAUUGUGGCUGUAGAAUUUAAAAAGCAAACAUGGGGGGGGUGGGGAAUCAUCUGUAUCCAGGGUAAGAAUGACCAAUAUUUUCACAUGGGAUCAUCCUAAUCACUGUAAACUUUUUGACAUUCCCGUAAAACACGUCUUAAAAGUUGACUGGAAUGAGCAGAAAUUACAUUCCUGAAAACAAGAACACUUGUGAUUUUUUUAUAAUAACCAACUAUAUAAUAUGUUUUUUUCUCCGUAUUUAUUGUGAUGUUGCCAAAUUUCUUUCUUUAGGUGAUAGAGACAUCAUUUCGAAUAACAAAUUGCUGAUAGUGAGAGGUACUUUACUUUAUCUUAGAAAGAAAGAAAAGGCCUGCUGCUGUAGCCAUGAUUUUGGUGCUUCAGUACUGUCAUUUCUGUUUUUCACAGUAAAAUUGGCAAAACUAAUGACUGAGAAAGUUAGUUAGCAAUGCACUUAACCAGCCUUACCCGAGGAAAGCAGCAUAAGUUCCAGUGGAUCCUUAGUUUUCUCUUCACUGCCUGCCAGGUUGUGUUGGGGUGGCAUCCUUAUCAGUGGUGUCUUUGUCUGCCUGGCUCUGAUAUCAUCCUGAUUUCGAAGAUCAUGCUGUUAGUCUCACAGCGGGGCACCCCUAUAAUAUAGACACUUGCAUGCCAACUCCUUCCAAAUUCAUUCACUGCUAUACCAGUGUCAGAUACUGUCUACACCAGCAAAUUGAAAACCAUCACAUCAGUAACUGACAUGGUGUCGGAAGAAACUCCAGUCUACAGAACCUUUGCACUCAGUAUGUGAGGUACAAUUGAGGCUGAUGAGAUACUGAGCUCAUUAUCAGUUCCUUCAUUGUUGAAUACUGCCUGCAAGUUGCUUAUUGGGAAUAAGAAAAAGUGUCCUUCUGUAUGUUUUGAUUUUUCACAUAACAGGCUUGGAGAAUCAGUUGUUGAUAGUGCAUGGAUUCUAUCAUCCAGGUCCGAUUAGCAUAAUUUUUCUGCGCCCUUUUUUUUUUUUUUUUUGCUCCAGUUCAAAUUCCUAGUGUUCUCAUAUGGUUUAUAUUACUGAAAAAUUAAUAUCUUUAAGCUAAAAUAUAAGGGAAAGGAAGAAGAGAAAUUUAGAUGUAAAAUGUGGGUCAGAUAUUUUAUAGGUUUCCAUUUAAUAUAUAUAUACACACAAAAUCCAGUAUAUUCUGAGUAGGUUCUUAGUUUUCUGAUUUCUACAUGUGUCUGCUAUGUGCAAAUGUAGUAUAUUAUUUACUACAUGGUUAUUGUGGUGUAGUGUGCAAAUGUUAGCAUGUGCAUUAUCCUGAUUACUGGACACAGUUUUAUUCUUAUCAGGAAUAGAACUUGCACAUGUACCAUACAAUUUUUUUUUUUUUAAUCACAAAGGAUGUAUUUCCCUAAGUAGCACUUUUGGAGCAGGGGAAGGAAGAAAACUGCUAUUCCCUAAUCCUCCUCCUAUAAGAUAUGCAUAUGCCUGAGGUGUAUAAAGACAUUUAGGUUAGUUAAUGGGCAUGUUAAUAAGAGCAUUGUGAUGCAAAUUCAUUUUCAAAAUGAAAAUAAUUUUUUCUUCCCCAAAAUGAGAAUAGUAGAAAUUUUGGUGAACUGAGCACCAUAGUUAUAUAAUAUUUCCCUGCGAAGGUCUAGUUUGAAGAAAAAAAAAACUUGAAAACAAACCUAUGAGGUUGAGCCUGGUUGCUAUAAAGACUUUGGGAUGGUAUGUGUUUCUGGGAUGAGCUAUAUAGAAAGUUUAGUUGACUGCUGGACCUUGGAUAUUCUUACUCGGUUCAAAAUACACAAAAACAAGCUGGUACAUAUGGUGCUUUAUAAUGCAGUCGAGAGUAAGAAUACAUGUUGCUGUAGCCCCAUUUCCUUUACAAACCCCCGCACAAUUUCAAAAGUGGAAGUUACCGUGGCCUCUGGUUUCCCAGUUCCUCCGUGGUGUAAUGAAGUCCCAGGUUUUAGAAGCUGAAGCCAAGCCUAGGGUAGCAUCGUCUGUACGGUGGUGAGGCCCAGCACAGCGGUAGCUGCCUAGUGGGAAUGACCCCCUGAGCAUGCAGAGCCCAGAGUCACUGUCCAUCUGCGUUCCCAGAGAACAAUUGUGAAGAGUCCUAGAACAGGAACUCUGAAUCAGACUGUCAGGGGCCUAUGUAGCCAAAAUGUUACUAAAUAUAAAAUUCCUGUCGUCUUCAGUCUUCAUGCUUUGUCACUGUAAAAAGAACAAAAAGCAUUUUUACUAUAAUUUAAAGGAGCUGCUUUUUUAUAGCACAUACUAUUUCGCUUUGUACUAUAUUUGAUAGUUGCAGAAUAAUUUAGACUGUAGAAAAACUUUGUUGUAUUUGUACUGUUCUUGAAUGUUUCAAAGAAAGUGCUUUACUUGGUUGCCAUAAUUUUCUUGUACUGCUGUAUUCCCCUCCUUCCCCUGCUUCAUGGAAACCUGAUAUGAUACAUAUUUUCAGUAGUUUUUUUUUUUUAAUGUGUGUUCGUUUGUACAAUUUUUUUUUUUUGGUCAGUAUUCUGAAUGUUUACAUCUGUUUGACAUUAGCCAUUUAAUGCCUUUUUUAAAGGCGGUAUUACUCCUACAGUGUAACAGCAAAAUGUGAAAUCAACCCAAACAUAACAUGCAUGACAAACACAGAUUGGGGGCGAAGGCCCUGAACCUACAUAGACAUUUUAUAUCAGCAUACAGAAAAGUAAAAUCCUCCUUCAGUCCUCUACCAAAGAAUAUAUUAUUCCCACAGGAAAAACUCAGAAAAGGUGUGUAAAAUCCUCAGAAGGGGGAGCAGUUGAUUCAGUAAGACUGCGACAAUUUAAUACUGUUACGCUUGCUUUGAUACCUGACUAAAUGUGACUGAGUGCAACAAGCAUUUAAGAAAAUUUUUAGACAGUGUUUUGUUUAGAAUUCAGGGAUCAUGCAUUCUUUAAUGGUGCUGUUUGUUUUUUAUUUCUUUUCUACAAAGAAAACAAGUGUUGCCUACAAAAGUGACUGCUCACAAUACCAUAAGUUAAAUGAAAUGAAAUGUUUGUCUCUUCAUGUUUCUCUGUCUUUCCCUUUCUCAAAGUAACAACUUGGGUUUCAAUAUUAAGAUAUUCUGGAGAAAAUAAAGAAAUUAAACAUGAAA